GCAGAGGAAGAUGGCGCCGCGGAGGGUCAGGUCGUUUCUGCGCGGGCUCCCGGCGCUGCUACUGCUGCUGCUCUUCCUCGGGCCCUGGCCCGCUGCGAGCCACGGCGGCAAGUACUCGCGGGAGAAGAACCAGCCCAAGCCGUCCCCGAAACGCGAGUCCGGAGAGGAGUUCCGCAUGGAGAAGUUGAACCAGCUGUGGGAGAAGGCCCAGCGACUGCAUCUUCCUCCCGUGAGGCUGGCCGAGCUCCACGCUGAUCUGAAGAUACAGGAGAGGGACGAACUCGCCUGGAAGAAACUAAAGCUUGACGGCUUGGACGAAGAUGGGGAGAAGGAAGCGAGACUCAUACGCAACCUCAAUGUCAUCUUGGCCAAGUAUGGUCUGGACGGAAAGAAGGACGCUCGGCAGGUGACCAGCAACUCCCUCAGUGGCACCCAGGAAGACGGGCUGGAUGACCCCAGGCUGGAAAAGCUGUGGCACAAGGCGAAGACCUCUGGGAAAUUCUCCGGCGAAGAACUGGACAAGCUCUGGCGGGAGUUCCUGCAUCACAAAGAGAAAGUUCACGAGUACAACGUCCUGCUGGAGACCCUGAGCAGGACCGAAGAAAUCCACGAGAACGUCAUUAGCCCCUCGGACCUGAGCGACAUCAAGGGCAGCGUCCUGCACAGCAGGCACACGGAGCUGAAGGAGAAGCUGCGCAGCAUCAACCAGGGCCUGGACCGCCUGCGCAGGGUCAGCCACCAGGGCUACAGCACUGAGGCUGAGUUCGAGGAGCCCAGGGUGAUUGACCUGUGGGACCUGGCGCAGUCCGCCAACCUCACGGACAAGGAGCUGGAGGCGUUCCGGGAGGAGCUCAAGCACUUCGAAGCCAAAAUCGAGAAGCACAACCACUACCAGAAGCAGCUGGAGAUUGCGCACGAGAAGCUGAGGCACGCAGAGAGCGUGGGCGACGGCGAGCGUGUGAGCCGCAGCCGCGAGAAGCACGCCCUGCUGGAGGGGCGGACCAAGGAGCUGGGCUACACGGUGAAGAAGCAUCUGCAGGACCUGUCCGGCAGGAUCUCCAGAGCUCGGCACAACGAACUCUGAAGGCAUUGGGGAGCCCAGCCCGGCAGGGAAGAGGCCAGCGUGAAGGACCUGGGCUCUUGGCCGUGGCAUUUCCGUGGACAGCCCGCCGUCAGGGUGGCUGGGGCUGGCACGGGUGUCGAGGCAGGAAGGAUUGUUUCUGGUGACUGCAGCCGCUGCCGUCGCGACACAGGGCUUGGUGGUGGUAGCAUUUGGGUCUGAGAUCGGCCCAGCUCUGACUGAAGGGGCUUGGCUUCCACUCAGCAUCAGCGUGGCAGUCACCACCCCAGUGAGGACCUCGAUGUCCAGCUGCUGUCAGGUCUGAUAGUCCUCUGCUAAAACAACACGAUUUACAUAAAAAAUCUUACACAUCUGCCACCGGAAAUACCAUGCACAGAGUCCUUAAAAAAUAGAGUGCAGUAUUUAAACCACCCGCUUGUUGGCUGGUCACUAAGUGUCCUGGUGGCUGGGGCCGGAGCCAGUGCUCUUGAAGGGAUCGCGUCAUAGCCAGCUUCCCCUCUGGGCCCUGUGGGUCUUUGCAGCCAACCUCCUUUUCCCGUGAGACGGCCCGGCCUGAUUUAAAGCCAAGAGCGCUUGAGUUGAGUUUGAGGGGAAGAUGUGGAGCGUGUGGUUCUGUGGACAGUCAGAGACUGUGGCCUGGGGGCAGCGUCUUUCAACUCUCACCUCUGCAGCUCAGGGACCUCGGGAGACCUCACCAAACCUGCAGGGCCUCCGUGUCCCUAAGUGUGCUGUGUAAAUGCCCCAUCUCAUGGGGGAGAGACAGCCACGGAGGCCUUCCUCUGACCAUAGCUGAUGGACUGGCGGUUGCUCAGGUCCGGCUCCGAGAAUGUUCCUGUGUCUGAGCCUGGAAGAGGCUCGGGUCUGGCUCCAGGCGUGGUUCCCUUCCCGUGUCUGAGCCUGGAAGAGGCUCGGGUCCGGCUCCGAGCGUGGUUCCCUUCCCGUGUCUGAGCCUGGAAGAGGCUCGGGUCCGGCUCCGAGCGUGGUUCCCUUCCCGUGUCUGAGCCUGGAAGAGGCUCGGGUCCGGCUCCGAGCGUGGUUCCCUUCCCGUGUCUGAGCCUGGAAGAGGCUCGGGUCCGGCUCCGAGCGUGGUUCCCUUCCCGUGUCUGAGCCUGGAAGAGGCUCGGGUCCGGCUCUGGGCGUGGUUCCCUUCCCGUGUCUGAGCCUGGAAGAGGCUCGGGUCCGGCUCUGGGCGUGGUUCCCGUGUCUGAGCCUGGAAGAGGCUCGGGUCCGGGUCCAGCUCCGAGCGUGGUUCCCGUGUUUGAACCUGGAAGAGGCUCCACCAGGCGUAUUGUGUUUUGACUGCAGCUGGAUCUUGGCUUGACUGUUGAGAUCUGCCAAACAUCCGCUAAGCUAUCAUUUCUGAGAAAGGUCAAGGCUAGAGGCAGCAUGUCGGGAGUUGGCGCAUCAGGGUUGGAAGGGCCCCAGGGUACAGCAUGUGGGUGCCUGUUCCUUUGUGGACUUGUGUGUGUGUGGCUGGUGGGGCGGGGGGUGGAUUCUGGUUCUUUUUUUUCCCAUUAUCCUGAGAGCCUUAAGGUACUCAGUGUGUUGGUGAGACUCAGCCCUGUCAUCUAGCAGAAGUGUGUUCCUUUUCAUUGCUGUAUAGUAUUCCAUUGCAUGACUGUCCUGUGCUCUGAUUUUAAUGCACUUUAUUGUGGGUGGAUAUUUGAGUUGCUUCCUUUCUGGGGUAAUAACACUCACUUGGAAAUAGCUGUGGUGAACACUCGUGUGGGGGUGGGGGUGGGGGCCAACUCUAGGAGCACCUAAUGGAUCUUACGAAGCGUGUUGUCCAAGUAUAGAGAUGAUUCCAAAGUGGUUGGACUGUGUUUCUUUCUCCCAGCUGGGUGGAAGGAGAACACUAGUGGAUUGCUGAGACUUGGUGCUCGGUAUUUUUAAUUAUGGACAGCCUGGCUGGCGUUUUGUGGUGUCUAAUUGCGGAGUAGCGUGUCUUACUGUAUAAUGGCCUCUUUUGUAUGUGGGAGACCAUGGUGUUGAGGGGAGGCAGUUACACAAAAAACCCAGAUACCGAGUGUUAGUUCCAUGGGUGUGGCUGGUCAUGGUGCGCACUCACGAAGGAUGUAGGUGAUGCCCUCCACUCCGCAGAGCCAGUCCCACAGGGGUACCCAUUCUGACUCCUACCACCGCAGCUCCCUACCUCCCGCCUGCCAUGGGUUCCACGUGCAUGGCUCUGGGCAGUCUGUGUCUUUGCGUGCGUCUGUGUAUGUCUGCGUGUAUCUGCUUACAUUCGCUCAGCAUCUGAGAUUCACCCAGGCUUUUGCGUGGAUCAGCGGCAGACUCCUGAUUGCCGCGUGGCGGCCUGUUGUGUGGGUGUGUGCCGCGUGUGUAUCCAGUCCCUACUCAGGAGUGUACGUUUCCAGUGUGGGUUGCAGUCAGGAUCCAUUUCUCCCUUAACUUUCAGAUUAUUUGCUGCAUAGGCUUUUUUCUCCUAAUUUGGCGCCUUUGUCAGAAAUCAACUGACCUACCUGUGUGGGUCUGUUUCUGUUUGUCCUUACGCUCUUGCCAUUGCCACACUUUAGACAAGGUCUUGCUCUGUCCCUCAGGCUGGAGUGCAGUAGCGUGAUCUCAGCUCACUGCACCCUUGACCUCCCAUACUCCAGCAAUCCCCUCGCCUCAGUCUCCUGAGUAGUAGCUGCGACCACAGGCGUGUGUCACCACACCCGGCUGAUUUUAUUUUUUUUAUUUUUAUUUUUUUUGUAGAGACGGGGUUUUACUAUGUUGCCCAGGCAGGUCUUGAUCUGGGCUCAAGUGAUGCUCCUGUCUCAGCCUCCCAAACUACUGGGAUUACAGGUUGUAGGUGUGAGCCAUGGUGCCCGGCCGCCACACUGUCUUGGCUACAGUUGGGUUUAUAAUAAACCCUGAAUCGAGGUGAUGUGCAUUUUCCAACUCUUCUUUUUAAAGAUUCUUGUGGCUGUUUAUGUCCUUGGUGUUUCCAUAUAUGUUUUACAAUCAGUGUCUCAAUUUCUACCAAAAAAACAUGCCUUCUGGAAUUUCAAUAGCAAUUCCCUUGAACGCAUUUUUGAAUACCUUUUCUGAAUGUCUUGAAUACAUGUUGGGAAGAAUCGGUGUCUUAACAGUCUCCAGUGUCCACGCGUUGACUGCCGUGUGUGACUCCAGUCGGCGUCUCAACAGUCUCCAGUGUCCACGCGUUGACUGCCGUGUGUGACUCCAGUCGGCGUCUCAGCAGUCUCCAGUGUCCACGCGUUGACUGCCGUGUGUGACUCCAGUCGGCGUCUCAGCAGUCUCCAGUGUCCACGCGUUGACUGCCGUGUGUGACUCCAGUCGGCGUCUCAGCAGUCUCCGGUGUCCACGCGUUGACUGCCGUGUGUGACUCCAGUCGGCGUCUCAACAGUCUCCGGUGUCCACGCGUUGACUGCCGUGUGUGACUCCAGUCGGCGUCUCAACAGUCUCCGGUGUCCACGCGUUGACUGCCGUGUGUGACUCCAGUCGGCGUCUCAACAGUCUCCGGUGUCCACGCGUUGACUGCCGUGUGUGACUCCAGUCGGCGUCUCAACAGUCUCCGGUGUCCACGCGUUGACUGCCGUGUGUGACUCCAGUCGGCGUCUCAACAGUCUCCGGUGUCCACGCGUUGACUGCCGUGUGUGACUCCAGUCGGCGUCUCAACAGUCUCCGGUGUCCACGCGUUGACUGCCGUGUGUGACUCCAGUCGGCGUCUCAACAGUCUCCGGUGUCCACGCGUUGACUGCCGUGUGUGACUCCAGUCGGCGUCUCAACAGUCUCCGGUGUCCAUGCGUUGACUGCCAUGUAUGACUCCAGGUAUUGAGUUCAUCUUCAACUUCUCCCAACAAUGAACUGGAGUUUUCUGUGCAUGUGUCUGGCAUGUUUUCCUUUAGAUCUAGUCCUAGGUGUUCGAUAUGCUAUUGAGGACUGUGUAUUUUUAUUUCAUUUGUCACCUGUGCGUGGUGCUUUAAUCCUGUGCCCUAAACUCCCGCCUUGGCCAUGGCGGUGUUUCUGUGGACUCGUGGGGUUUCCGUGUGCACACGCGUGUCCUCUGUCUGACAGUGGCUUUGCUUCCCCUUGUCAGUCUGUGCCUCGGCUUCUCACUGCACUGGUGAGGUGAGCCGGCGCUCGCUAAUCUUAUUCCCAGUCUCGGUGAACAUGGGCUCAGUCUCUCCCGGCUCAGUGUUGGGUUUGCACUGGUGCACUUACAGGCAGAAGAGCUUCCUCAUUUGCUGAGGGCUUUUCCUGAAUCCGUGUUGAAUGUGGUCAGCUGCCUUUCCUGCACCUAGUGAGAUGCUCAUGAGGUCACUUCCUUACCGCAUUACUGUAGUGAAUUACGCUGACUUUCAUAUGCCAAGAUGACCUGGCAUUUCCAGGUAAGUCCCUGUGGCCAUGGUGCAUUGGCCUUUUCUCUGCAUGGCCAGAUGAGAUUUGCUCAUACCGGGCUAAGGACCUCCUGUGUAGGAAUGCUCUUGAGGGACACUGGGCUUGGAUGUUCAUUGUCUUGUCAUGUGAUGUGUCUGUCAUGGUUUGAUAUUGCAUUAAGUGGGCCUCCUGAAACAAGUUCUGCCAUAGUUUGUAUAGGAUUGGCAUUAUUUGUUUCAUAGAGAUGUGAUGGGUGAGGCCAUCUAUGCCUGCCAUUUUCUUUUUGCUUAGGUUUUUCAUUAAGAACUUGAUUUUUAAAAAUAGACAUGAGGCCUGGCAUGGUGGCUCACGCUUGUAAUCCCAGCACUUUGGGAGGCCAACGUGGAUGGAUCACCUGAGGUCAGGAGUUUGAGACCAACCUAGUCAACAUGGUGAAACCCCGUCUCCAUUAAAAAUAUAAAAAUUAGCAGGGUGUGGUGGUGCAUGCCUGUAAUCCCAGCUACUCUGGAGGCUGAGGCAGGAGAAUCACUUGAACUCAGGAGGUGGAGGUUGCAGUGAGCUGAGAUCACACCACUGCACUCCAGCCUGGGCAACAGAGCGAGGCUCUGUCUCAAAAAAAAAGACAUGAGGCUUUUGGAUUUUCUGUUUCUUCCUUUGUCAUUUUUUUAAAGAUAGGUUUGUCGCAGAAUUUCAUCUAAGUUAUCAAAACAAUUUACAUAAAUCAUUCACAGUAUCCUCUGUGCAGUGAUGUCCAUUCUCAUUCCUGCUCUGGGCCAUUUGUGUUUUCUUUUCCCCCUGAUCAGACUAGCUAAGAGUUUAUCAUUUUUACAGAUAUUUUCCCCAAAGAAACCUACUUUUGGGUCCAUUGAUUUUUUUUUUCUAUUGUUUUCUUUUUCAUUGACUUUUGCUCUUUUCUUAUGAAUUUCCUUUCUUCUACCUAUUUUGUGUUCAAUUUGCUGUCCUUGUUUUAGGUUCUUUUGAUAGAGGCUUAGAUCAUUGAUGAAGAAUAUGAAAGAAUGGGAUAAUACAGUUAAAAACUUGGUCUACUUAUGCCCAUUAGAGAAAACAUUCUUAAGCACGCAUGGAAUCUUUUAAAAAUGGACGAGGUACUAGGACCCAAAGCAAAUGUCAGUAAUUCGCAGAUGAUAAUGUAUAAAUAUAUGAUAUGUAGGUAAAUAAUACAAAUCACAUUCUUUGGCCAGAGUGCAAUUGAGGAGGAAAUCAGUAACAAAAAGACAAUUAAAUCCAUUUGAUUCUUUUGUUUUCGUUUUGUAGUAACUUGCACUUCCCUGGUGCCAGAGGCAUGACACCUUUUUGUCUGCUCUUGGCCAUUUGGGUGGCGUCUUUGGGAAGGGCCUACUUAAUUCUUUUGCCUAUUUAAAAAACUGGGUCUUGGAAAUCUUGUCUUUUUUUUUGAGUCAGGAUCUUUCUCGCACAGGCUUGGAGUGCAGUGGUGCGAUCAUAGCUCACUGCAACCUCAAACUCCUGGGCUCAAGCGAGCCUCCCACCUCGGUCUUCUGAGUAGCUGGGACUACAGGCAUGCAUCACUAUGCUCUGCUAAUUUAAAGAAAAGGUUUUUUUUAUAGAGACUGGGUCUCGCUGUGUUGCCCAGGCUGGUCUCGGAGUCCUGGUCUCAAGUGAUUCACCUGCCUCCACCUCGCGGAGUGCCAGGAUUACAGGUGGCGGGAGCCGCCACACCCAGCCUGGUCUUAGCGUUAUUCCCAGGUCUAGGUGUGAGUCCUUCCUCAGAUAUGUGUUGUGAAUAAUUUCCGAUCCUCUGGCUUGCUAUUUUACUUUCUUAAUGGUUAUCUUUUGGAAAGCAAAGGUUUCCAGUUUGAUGAAAUCUAAUUUUUAUUUUUUAUUUUUCCGUUCUAGUGGUCUUUCUAUUUUCUCAUCAAAUUGAGACUUUGGGGAAACUACACAGCAGCAAACCAGGAUAUAUCCUCUUAAAAACAGCUCGAGCCGGCCGGGUGCGGUGGCUCAUGCCUGGAAUCCCAGCACUUUGGGAGGUGGAGGUGGGCGGAUCACGUGAGGUCAGGAGUUUGAGACCAGCCUGGCCAACAUGGUGAAACCCCAUCUCUACUAAAAAUAAAAAAUUAGCCAGGCAUGGUGGCAGGCACCUGUAAUCCCAGCUACUUGGGAGGCUGAGGCAGGAGAAUGGCUUGAACCUGGGAGGCAGAGGUUGCAGUGAGCCGAGAUCGCGCCAUUGCACUCCGGCCUGGGGACAAGAGCAAGACUUCGCCUCAAAAAAAAAAAAAAACCCAGCUUGAGCCAAGUGUGGGUGGCUCCCGCCUGGAAUCCCAGCACUUUGGGAGGCUGAGGCGGGCAGAUCACUUGAGGCCAGGAGUUUGAGACCAGCCUGGCCAACAUCACAAAAUCCCAUCUCUACUAAAAAUACAAAAAUUAACCAGGAGUGGUGGCAGCAUCUGCCUAUAAUCCCAGCUACUCGGGAGCCUAAGGCACGAGAAUCACUUGAAGCUGGGAGACAGAGUUUGCAGUGAGCCAAAAUCGUGCCAUUGCUCUCCAGCAUGGAUAACAGAGCAAGACUCUGUCUCAAAAAAAAAAAGCUUGAAAAUUUAAAAAUAUCUCAAUAAUUAUGAGAUGCAGUGAUUUUUUUUUUACUUCCCUAAGCUGGGUUUCCAGGUAUCUCUAGGUUCAGCUCCUCCGGGGCUGGAAGUACAUGAAGGGCAGCAUUGCCCACCUUGACCAGAGCAGGCUCGGAGCAGGGCAGUGGAAGAGCUGGUCCCAGCUCAGCCCAGCCUGCUGGGUCAGCAUCCAUCUGAAAGGUCAUCUCUACCCAGGAACUUGAUGGCUUCCAGCUCCACCCUAACAGAAACCUCCCCAGCAUCUUGCCGAGUUGUAAUCCAGGGUGGUGGUAUAGACGGUCUUGGGGUAGCUGGUAUAGACGGUCUUGGCGUAGCUGGUAUAGACGGUCUUGGGGUAGCUGGUAUAGACGGUCUUGGGGUAGCUGGUAUAGACGGUCUUGGGGUAGCUGGUAUAGACGGGCUUGGGGUAGCUGGUAGUGGUGCUCAGGAGGCGUGUGGGCUGCUGGUGCAGCUGGAAGCGCACCUCAGCCAUGGUGUUGUGCCAGGUGUGGUUGGGGAUGCAGGGGACGUUCCGGCCGCAGGAGGCCCCUGCCAGGCACAGGCAGCUGCGCGGUGUGGAAGAAGUGCCGCUCGGAGUCAUGCUUGACAAGGAAGUACACCUUACUCCUCUCAGUGGUGAGGGGUCAAACCACUCCUUCCCAGCGAUGGGGCCAGCAGCCUGGCGAGGGCUAGGCACCGGGGAGGGAUGCUGGAUUUGGAGCUGGGGGGAAGGGGUCACCCUGCAUUGGGCUCCAGUGCUCCGGGUGCCAUGCCUGCUCCCCCACCACUGCCACCGCAGCCGCUGCGGGACACCAGGGGCUGGGGCUGAAGAGCAGCCUCGAGCUGGGCUGUCCAGGACACGGUCGCCCUUCUUCCUCGUGUCCGUGAGCUCAGGCACAACCUGCAGCUUAGCCAGCCCACUAUGGCUGCGUGCGUGGCAGGACCCGGGCCACCAUGGCUGCGUGCAUGGUAGGGCACAUGAUUAUUUUAGCCUCUGGUAUCACUAACCAUCCCUAAAGUCUCCAAUGGUCUGUUCCUGUCUUUCCCUCUGGUUCACUUGUGGGGUCAUGUUGUCUUCUGUUCUUUGUUAUUUAUUUUUUUCUUGAGACGGAGUCUUGCUCUGUCGCCCAGGCUGGAGUGCGUUGGUGCGAUCUCGGCUCACUGCAACCUCUGCCUCCCAGGUUCAUGCGAUUCCCCUGCCUCAGCCUCCCAAGUAGCUGGGAUUAUGGGCACCUGCCACCAUACCCAGCUAAUUUUUCUGUGUGUGUGUGUGUUUUGUUUUUUGGUUUUUUUUUUUUUUUUUUUGAGAUGGAAUCUCAAUUGCUCAGGCUGCAGUGCAAUGGCGCAAUCUUGGCUCACUGCAACCUCCACCUCCUGGGUUCAAGAAAUUCUCCUGCCUCAGCCUCGCAAGUAGCUGGGAUUACAGGCCCCUACCACCACAGUGGGCUAAUGUUUGUAUUUUUAGUAGAGACAGGGUUUCACCAUGUUGGCCAGGCUGGUCUCGAACUCCUGACCUCAGGCAAUCCGCCCACCUCGGCCUCCCAAAGUGCUGGGAUUGUAGGCAUGAGCCACCAUGCCUGGCCUAAUUUUUCUGUUUUUAGUAGAGACAGGACUUCACCAUGUUGGCCAGGCUGGUCUCAAAUUCCUGACCUCAAGUGAUGUGCCCACCUCGGCUGCCCAAAGUGCUGGGAUUACAGGCAUGAGCUUCUGUGCCCGGCCUGAACUGUUAAGUGUUUGUGAAGAAUUAUUUGGGGGCCUAUUUGAGAGCUGUUAUAUGGAUCAUCCUCCUGGAGAGGGUUCUUAAGCCUCUGAGACCGGGUUUGGGGCUGAGGCUUUCUGACCCACACAAGUCAUGCUGACCCCUGAAGGGCCGCAGGCCAGAUCUUGCCAGGUGAGCACUUUCCCCGCUCACAUUCAGGAUAGGGCGAGGGGGUUGGUACCGAUUCACCCUCAGGGCCUAGAUUUGGGGGCUUCAGCUUGCUGCAGAUAGGUGCUCCCUUCACUCUCACCUGAGGCUGGGCUGGAGCCUGGUGUCUGCCCCACCCUGCUGGUCAGCCCCCUAGGACCUGAGCCCCGUAAGCCUGGACUGGCCACGCCCUGGGGCAGCAGCACUGGGUGCUUGGCGCUCACGACCUUCCUGGGCCCCUGGGUCCCUCACUUCUCCCUUGUUUCUACCUUCCUGGCUUGUCAGAUUCCCACAGCUCUUAAGGAGAAAUUCAGUAUUUACUGCAGCAUGUGUUUUCAGUGUGAUGGUUCAUCUAGGUACCCUAGCCUGUCAUUGCUGGAGUUGGAAAUCUCUGUUGUCUGCUGUUGUUUUGUGAAACAAGCGCGUGAGGUUAUAAGUUUCCCUCAACGUACCACACUAACCACAUUUCCCUAAGUUUUGAUGUGUAGUGUUUUCACUGCCAUUCAGUUCAAAAUAUUUUCUCAUUUCAAGUA